GGCGCUGACCAUGCCCAGCGGCUGCCGCUGCCUGCAUCUCGUGUGCCUGUUGUGCAUUCUGGGGGCUCCCGGUCAGCCUGUCCGAGGGUUGAGUCCGCUCAGUUACUGGAACCCCAAUCCUCUCCUGAGUCCCGCAUCCCAGCGAGCUGUGCCCUGACUCAGACUCACCCCUCCCACAUCAAUCUCUUGCAGCCGAUGACUGCAGCUCCCACUGUGACCUGGCCCACGGCUGCUGUGCACCUGACGGCUCCUGCAGGUACCUGUCCUGAGCACGUGCCCCCAAACCCUUUGGUACCCAUUUCUAAGCCCUUCACGUGCACAACAGUGUCUAGGGGCUUCAGACUCUACUCUUCAUGCCUCAUCACUCCUAUGGCUGACUGGCCAGUCCCCCUUUCCCCUUUACCUCACCUCUCUUGCUUCUUCUAGUUUUUAUCUCCCCACUUCUUUAAUCUCCCAAGUCUGAUCCAGGGAUUGUCUGAACUCCUGACAGGGAGAGAGACCUAAAGCUUGAGAGAGCUUGGGGAUUGGGUGCCAUGAGGAAAUGGAAAGAUAAAGGAAAAAGGGAAAGAGAAAUGGUUUAGCCUGGAAAAGAAAUGCUGCAGGGAGAGUUGCUGGGGAGAAACACUUACAAUGAAAGAGGAUCUUUCUUGAUGAGUUUGAGUAGUUGACUCACUGGGAGAUUGGGCAAAUUCUGUAGCAGGAGGAAAGUGGACAUAAGGAAAUGAGUUGAUGAGGCAGGUAGUUCAAUUGGCUGGGGGUCUUUGAGACUCUUCACCCCUGGAGGGCUUUUAAAAUAUGGGUCAAGUGUUUGCCCUGGAAUCAUGGUGGGAGGAUAGUCCUGAUGACCUUUUUUGUUUUUAUUUUUAUUUUUUGUUUUUGAGACAGAGUCUCGCUUUGUUGCCAAGGCUGGAGUGCAGUGGCGCGAUCUCAGCUCACUGCAGCCUCUGCCUCUUGUGUUCAAGUUCCCCUGCCUCAGCCUCCUCAAUAAUGGAUUACAGAUGCACACCACCAUGCCCGGGUAAUUUUUUGUAUUUUUUGUAGAGACGGGGUUUCACCCAGUUGGCCAGGCUGGUCUUGAACUCCUGACCUCAAGUGAUCCACCUGCCUCGACCUCCCAAAGUGCUGGGAUUACAGGCGUGAGCAACCACGCCCCGGCCCUGAUGGCCUUUCAAGGUCAUUCUUCUUUAAAUGUUUGUGAGCACCUCAGACAUGCCAGGAGGGGUACUGGAGGCAUUUACAGACAUCUUAUUUCUUCCUCUACUCAACCCUGCAAGGUGUAUCCCCAAUUUACAGGUGAGAAAACUGAGGCUCAGGUUAAAGUACAGAACCAGGGUUUGAGUGCUGGUGUCUGAUGGUCUGAUUCCGUAUAUGUGUCCUAUGACCCUGCACAGUCCUACACCUACCUGGGACAGGUCUGCUUUCCCUUAGGGGCUGUCAUAUGUCCUCUUGGUUUCUAGAAGCUCUGGUUCUGUCUCCUCCAUUUCUUCACAUCCAUGACCCAGAGCCCUGACCCUGUGCUUCUCCCCGUCAGGUGUGACCCGGGCUGGGAGGGGCUGCACUGUGAGCGCUGUGUGAGGAUGCCUGGCUGCCAGCACGGUACCUGCCACCAGCCAUGGCAGUGCAUCUGCCACAGUGGCUGGGCAGGCAAGUUCUGUGACAAAGAUGAACAUAUCUGUACCACGCAGUCCCCCUGCCAGAAUGGAGGCCAGUGCAUGUAUGACGGGGGCGGUGAGUACCAUUGUGUGUGCUUACCAGGCUUCCAUGGGCGUGACUGCGAGCGCAAGGCUGGACCCUGUGAACAGGCAGGCUCCCCAUGCCGCAAUGGCGGGCAGUGCCAGGACGACCAGGGCUUUGCUCUCAACUUCACGUGCCGCUGCUUGGUGGGCUUUGUGGGUGCCCGCUGUGAGGUAAAUGUGGAUGACUGCCUGAUGCGGCCUUGUGCUAACGGUGCCACCUGCCUUGACGGCAUAAACCGCUUCUCCUGCCUCUGUCCUGAGGGCUUUGCUGGACGCUUCUGCACCAUCAACCUGGAUGACUGUGCCAGCCGCCCAUGCCAGAGAGGGGCCCGCUGUCGGGACCGUGUCCACGACUUCGACUGCCUCUGCCCCAGUGGCUAUGGUGGCAAGACCUGUGAGCUUGUCUUACCUGUCCCAGACCCCCCAACCACAGUGGACACCCCUCUAGGGCCCACCUCAGCUGUAGUGGUACCUGCCACGGGGCCAGCCCCCCACAGCGCAGGGGCUGGUCUGCUGCGGAUCUCAGUGAAGGAGGUGGUGCGGAGGCAAGAGGCUGGGCUAGGUGAGCCUAGCUUGGUGGCCCUGGUGGUGUUUGGGGCCCUCACUGCUGCCCUGGUUCUGGCUACUGUGUUGCUGACCCUGAGGGCCUGGCGCCGGGGUGUCUGCCCCCCUGGACCCUGUUGCUACCCUGCCCCACACUAUGCUCCAGCGUGCCAGGACCAGGAGUGUCAGGUUAGCAUGCUGCCAGCAGGGCUCCCCCUGCCACGUGACUUGCCCCCUGAGCCUGGAAAGACCACAGCACUGUGAUGGAGGUGGGGGCUUUCUGGCCCCCUUCCUCACCUCUUCCACCCCUCAGACUGGAGUGGUCCGUUCUCACCACCCUUCAGCUUGGGUACACACACAGAGGAGACCUCAGCCUCACACCAGAAAUAUUAUUUUUUUAAUACACAGAAUGUAAGAUGGAAUUUUAUCAAAUAAAACUAUGAAAAUGCAA